AACUCAAGUCGCUGGUCAUCCUCAGAGCGGUGUUGGCCCGGGGCCUUCAGUGGCCUUUGUGUCUGGGUGAGAGGAACCCUGGAUGGCCACUCUGCCCUGAGUGUGUGGGUCCCCAGAAGUGCUGGGUUAGGGGGCACGGAGGGCCAGAAAGUCCCCUUUGGAGCGCUGGACUCUCUCGCUGACUCCUACCCCACCCCGGCCUGGGGUUUCAGAGAAGGGGUCCAGGCAGGAGUGUCAUCUUUUCUCAAUGGGGAUGUGGCUUCAGUCUCUGUCCAGGUGG